GCAGCUCCGCGCACCCGGCAGCGGCGGCGGUGCAGCCUCGGGCGUUCGGACAGCCUCCGAGCCCAUGGCGGGGAGCGACGUGGACAGCGAGGGCCCCGCACGGAGGGGCGGCGCGGCGCGGCGUCCGGGGGCCCCUGGCGGGCCAGGAAGCGAGGCGGCAGCCGGCUGCCCGGAGCCGCUGUCCACUGCUGAAGCGCCGGCUGAGAGCGCCACGCUGCCCGCCUGGAUGCGCCUCUACUUCUACGGGAUGCACGGGAUCACCCUGGACGUGCUGGUGUCCUCGGCCCGGCGCUUCGCCCGCAGCCCGGACCUGCGGAUGCUAGGCUUCUCCUCGCCCUACCGCUGCCUGCUGCACUCGCUCACCCAUUUCGCCCUGGAGAAGGUGUACCUGCAGCAGCGGCGCUGUCCCAACGCCUUCGUCUUCAAUUUCCUCCUCUACCCCUCGGCCCACGUGGGGCUGCAGACCCUAGCGGGCCAGGCGCUACUACUCAGCCUGGGCGGCGGGGCGGGGGUCGCGGUGGCGCCAGGGGCGCUGGACCUGGCGCUGCAGUACGUGCUGGCGCUCUACCACUGCCAAGUGUUCCUGAAGCGCUUCCUGCGCUUGCGGUACGGGCGACAGAGGCGGCGGCAGCAGCAACAGCAGCAGCAGCAGCAGCAGCAGCAGCGGAGGGGCGCGCUCCCCGUCCCUCCCGGCGCCCGGGUCCCUACUGCGGCCGGAGCCCGGCGGCGACGACCCCGUGGCCCCAGGGGCGCCGGGGGAGCCCCCAGCCAGGGGCUGCCCGACCUACCCCGCUUUCUUUUCUUCGGAAUGCACGGCUUUCUGGAUGAGAUCUUCUUCACCUUCUUCUUCAACGUACUGGGGCAGGGGGACGGGACAACCAGCGGCCACACGUCGCUCUGGUCCUUCUUUAUGUACGGCAGCUGCAGUUUCGUGGUGGAAAAGCUCUACUUCCACCUCCACUACAGCCGCGGUUGGGGCACUUGGAAGCGGGUGCCCAUCUACGUGAUCUUCAUCUACGUGUGGGAGCUGUCCUGGGGUCUGGGACUCCGCACGUGCGGGGCUUGUUCCUGGGACUAUUCUCACUACCCGCUCAAUUUUAUGGGCCUCAUCACCCUGAUGUAUUUACCUGGCUGGAUAUUCCUUAGUGUGUACCAGGACCUAAUUUCCAACGUGUUGUGGAGGGUGCAGUACGUACCAGCUAACUAAAACCAAAAAAGAAAGAAAGAAAAGGAAAAAGUCACUGGAUUCCCACGAAUGGAUGCGAUUUAUUUUUACACAUUUAAAAUGAAGUGGGUUUUUUAGUCCUUUAAUUUUUAUACGCUUUACUAAACUCUUCCAAAUUGUUUUAUUCCACCUUUUAGUUUUUCUAUUUGAAACCCGUGUAUAAUAUACUUUGAAACACUACUCGAAACAUAAUUCAAAGUACUUUAUUUGCCAAUGUUUUAAAACAUUUACAAGCCCAAACGUUUACACGCCCAAACAGCAAAACCGUUAUACCUUAACAUCAGAAUGAUGUAGUAGUGUUUACCCAUCUGGCAACAGAUGAGUGACAGCUACUAAUUUUUUUUUUUUUGGCGGGGGGGGAUCUUUAAAUCAGAGACCAGUGAUUUUUACAAGAUUUGGCUAAAUUUUCUGAUUCAGUGAUUUGUUUUACUUUCUUUUUAAUCUAAUUUCAUUUUAAUUCCUUGCCAUAUUUACCAAUGACUGAAGAAACUCAAUGUCUUGUACUCUUGAGACUACAGUUAAUAGCUCUUAAAGUGCCUCCGUCUAGCACACAAGUGAAAAGAGGCUGAAAAAUGUGAAAGCACGUUCUAUGAACAGAUUUUUAAAUGAGAGGUCUUUUCUAGCAACUCACACAGGUGACACUGUGUUAAGAUAUUUGAUCUCCAUCCUGGAAAUGAUUGCUUUCCAAUGUGGGUAAGCCUUAAACAGCAGGUGUGUUAACGUUGAUCAGAUCCUGUGUUAUCUAUGGCUGUAAAUUUUUGUUACUGUGCAAUAAUGUAAAAUGUUUACCUUACAUAGCCGAGGGCCAAGUGAAAUUAUAUCACCUUCCACAGUGUUCUAACUCCAAGGACCCUUUUCUACAUGGAACUUCAAGGGCAGAAACAUUACCUUUGAAUAAAAUGAACCUGAAUGUUCACUCUAA